GUUUCCGGCCCCUUUCUCUGGAGGAUCUCCGCGCGUGGCGAGUCUGUGUCCUCCCUGUCCCCCAGAGCAGACACCCUCUCUGUGUCUGGACCGGGGAGGAGCAGACGCUGGACAGGUUUCUGGUAGAAUGCUGGCAAUUUCCAGGAAGAUACGUGGAGAACGGAAAGGUUGCUACACCCAAAUAGUGAAGCAAAGGCUAUGAUUAUGGAGGAUUGGACCUGCAAACUCCAGAACAGAGCAACCUUGUAAAAUGUGUGUGGGCAGCACAGAGAACUUGGGCAAGUUAACAGUUUCCUCAUCUGUGAAUACUGAUUUAUGGAAAGCACCUGGUGCGUGUUCUGCCCUCUGAGGACCCUGCCCUUUCCCAAAAGGGGUAUCUUAAGAAGGAAAAUAUGGCUGCUCUUUGCCGGACAGCAGAGUCCCAGAACCCCAUGCAGGUGUUUCAGGGCUUUAUGUCAUUCAAGGAUGUGGCUGUGAACUUCACUAGGAAGAAUGGAGAGAACUGGACCUUGCUCAGAGAGUCUUGUACAGGGAUGUAAUGCUGGAGAACUAUAGGAACCUGGUCUCCUUGGUAGGAUUUCCAUUUUCCAAACCUGGUAUCAUCUCCUAGUUGGAAGAAGUGGUAAGCCCACGAACACAAAUGCAGGAGGGAGAGGUGCCAAGAAGCAGCGGUACACAGCAGGCACAGAGACACGUGGUCUUCAGCAGAGCCUAUGGGGUUCAGAUGAUUCACAUAAGAAUAGAAGUUUCAGGGCUGGACCUGGGGAGGCAGCCUGAGCCUGAGCCGGCUGUCCUGAGCCUGAGUACUCUAGCUGCCUUGUCGUCAUCGCAUCUGGCUGCCAUCCAGCGCCAGCACACAGUAAUGAGUGGCCGAGCUUCCUCUGGGAGGGAGGAAACAGUUAAAAUCUUGCAGCAGCUGCAAUCAUCUAGGCGUGGUUCUCUUGUCUGACUUGGGCUGCACAGAUCCUGGGCCAAGGGACAGAAGAAAGACAGCCUAGGAGCAGAGCCUCCCAGAUGGCUGAGUUGGAUCUAAUGGCUCCAGGGCCACUGCCCAGGGCCACUGCUCAGCCCCCAGCCCCUCUCAGCCCAGACUCUGGGUCACCCAGCCCAGAUUCUGGGUCAGCCAGCCCAGUGGAAGAAGAGGACGUGGGCUCCUCGGAGAAGCUUGGCAGGGAGACGGAGGAACAGGACAGCGACUCUGCAGAGCAGGGGGAUCCUGCUGGUGAGGGGAAAGAGGUCCUGUGUGACUUCUGCCUUGAUGACACCAGAAGAGUGAAGGCAGUGAAGUCCUGUCUAACCUGCAUGGUGAAUUACUGUGAAGAGCACUUGCAGCCGCAUCAGGUGAACAUCAAACUGCAAAGCCACCUGCUGACCGAGCCAGUGAAGGACCACAACUGGCGAUACUGCCCUGCCCACCACAGCCCACUGUCUGCCUUCUGCUGCCCUGAUCAGCAGUGCAUCUGCCAGGACUGUUGCCAGGAGCACAGUGGCCACACCAUAGUCUCCCUGGAUGCAGCCCGCAGGGACAAGGAGGCUGAACUCCAGUGCACCCAGUUAGACUUGGAGCGGAAACUCAAGUUGAAUGAAAAUGCCAUCUCCAGGCUCCAGGCUAACCAAAAGUCUGUUCUGGUGUCGGUGUCAGAGGUCAAAGCGGUGGCUGAAAUGCAGUUUGGGGAACUCCUUGCUGCUGUGAGGAAGGCCCAGGCCAAUGUGAUGCUCUUCUUAGAGGAGAAGGAGCAAGCUGCGCUGAGCCAGGCCAACGGUAUCAAGGCCCACCUGGAGUACAGGAGUGCCGAGAUGGAGAAGAGCAAGCAGGAGCUGGAGAGGAUGGCGGCCAUCAGCAACACUGUCCAGUUCUUGGAGGAGUACUGCAAGUUUAAGAACACUGAAGACAUCACCUUCCCUAGUGUUUACGUAGGGCUGAAGGAUAAACUCUCGGGCAUCCGCAAAGUUAUCACGGAAUCCACUGUACACUUAAUCCAGUUGCUGGAGAACUAUAAGAAAAAGCUCCAGGAGUUUUCCAAGGAAGAGGAGUAUGACAUCAGAACUCAAGUGUCUGCCGUUGUUCAGCGCAAAUAUUGGACUUCCAAACCUGAGCCCAGCACCAGGGAACAGUUCCUCCAAUAUGCGUAUGACAUCACGUUUGACCCGGACACAGCACACAAGUAUCUCCGGCUGCAGGAGGAGAACCGCAAGGUCACCAACACCACGCCCUGGGAGCAUCCCUACCCGGACCUCCCCAGCAGGUUCCUGCACUGGCGGCAGGUGCUGUCCCAGCAGAGUCUGUACCUGCACAGGUACUAUUUUGAGGUGGAGAUCUUCGGGGCAGGCACCUAUGUUGGCCUGACCUGCAAAGGCAUCGACCGGAAAGGGGAGGAGCGCAACAGUUGCAUUUCCGGAAACAACUUCUCCUGGAGCCUCCAAUGGAACGGGAAGGAGUUCACGGCCUGGUACAGUGACAUGGAGACCCCACUCAAAGCUGGCCCUUUCCGGAGGCUCGGGGUCUAUAUCGACUUCCCGGGAGGGAUCCUUUCCUUCUAUGGCGUAGAGUAUGAUACCAUGACUCUGGUUCACAAGUUUGCCUGCAAAUUUUCAGAACCAGUCUAUGCUGCCUUCUGGCUUUCCAAGAAGGAAAACGCCAUCCGGAUUGUAGAUCUGGGAGAGGAACCCGAGAAGCCAGCACCGUCCUUGGUGGGGACUGCUCCCUAGACUCCAGGAGCCAUAUCCCAGACCUUUGCCAGCUACAGUGAUGGGAUUUGCAUUUUAGGGUGAUUUGGGGGCAGAAAUAACUGCUGAUGGUAGCUGGCUUUUGAAAUCCUAUGGGGUCUCUGAAUGAAAACAUUCUCCAGCUGCUCUCUUUUGCUCCAUAUGGUGCUGUUCUCUAUGUGUUUGCAGUAAUUCUUUUUUUUUUUUUUGAGACGGAGUCUCGCACUGUUGCCCAGGCUGGAGAGCAGUGGCGCGAUCUUGGCUCACUGCAAGCUCCGCCUCCCGAGUUCAAGCAAUUCUCCUGCCUCAGCCUCCCGAGUAGCUGGGAUUACAGGUGCCUGCCACCACACCCAGCUAAUGUUUUGUAUUUUUAGUAGAGAUGGGGUUUCACCAUGUUGGCCAGGCAGAUCUCAAACUCCUGACCUCGUGAUGCACCCACCUCGGCCUCCCAAAGUGCUGGGAUUACAUGCGUGAGCCACUGCGCCCUGCCUGUUUGUAGUAAUUUUUAGGCACCAAAUCUCCCUCAUCUUCUAGUGCCAUUCUCCUCUCUGUUCAGGUAAAUGUCACACUGUGCCCAGAAUGGAUGACCAGGAACCUUAAAGAGUGGCUGAAAAGAUUGCAGAGUUAUCAUAAUAAAUUGCUAACUUGCGUA